ACAAGCCGCUUUAGGAGCGAGGUUCGGAGCCAUCGCUGCUGCCUGCUGAUCCGCGCCUAGAGUUUGACCAGCCACUCUCCAGCUCGGCUUUCGCGGCGCCGAGAUGCUGUCCUGCCGCCUCCAGUGCGCGCUGGCUGCGCUGUCCAUCGUCCUGGCCCUGGGCUGUGUCACCGGCGCUCCCUCGGACCCCAGACUCCGUCAGUUUCUGCAGAAGUCCCUGGCUGCUGCCGCGGGGAAGCAGGAACUGGCCAAGUACUUCUUGGCAGAGCUGCUGUCUGAACCCAACCAGACGGAGAAUGAUGCCCUGGAACCUGAAGAUCUGUCCCAGGCUGCUGAGCAGGAUGAAAUGAGGCUUGAGCUGCAGAGAUCUGCUAACUCAAACCCGGCUAUGGCACCCCGAGAACGCAAAGCUGGCUGCAAGAAUUUCUUCUGGAAGACUUUCACAUCCUGUUAGCUUUCUUAACUAGUAUUGUCCAUAUCAGACCUCUGAUCCCUCGCCCCCACACCCCAUCUCUCUUCCCUAAUCCUCCAAGUCUUCAGCGAGACCCUUGCAUUAGAAACUGAAAACUGUAAAUACAAAAUAAAAUUAUGGUGAAAUUAUGAAAAA